GAUCUGUGAAGAUAGUUUCUAUUAAAGAAGAAGUACCAGGAAAUCCCAUAUGCCACCGUAGACCUGCCUUUCUGGAUACCAUUUACUACUCCAUACUCCAGCCGCCAUGCACAAUGGUUGUGUAUGAGGCUCCUGUGAUCAUUAACAGGAGUAGAAGCUGGGCUCAGACACUCUGGCACUUGCAUAGGUCAAGGGGUGUGUUGUGCUCUUGCAACAAAUCCCACAUAGACAUCCAUAUGCAUAUUGUCCCACCGUCCCCUAAGCAGAAACCAGGGUUAAGUACAGAAUAGUCCCGGGAACAUUUUGGUUGCCCGGCCUUAGGUGAGCCUUUCUGGGGCUGGGAUUUUGACACCAUCUGCUCCAUUGUUUCUAAACUGCUGUGUUCUGGCGCAUCAAUUGUUUCAUCACAUUAUCAUCACGGAAAGCUUGGUCUCCCUCAAAACAUGAACCGGAAGGAAGGCUUGGAGAAGCAAUCUGACCAAGAUCACAUCCCUUUUUUUUUUUCGGAGAUGGAGGGGGAGUCUCACUGUGUUACCCCAGCUAGUCUUGAACUCCUGGCCUCAGGGAUCCACCUGCCUCAGCCCCCCAAGUAGCUGGGAUUACAAGUGCUAGCCACUGAACCUGGCCAGAAUCACAUCAUUUUUAAAUGGCUGAACUAGGAUUUAAACCCAUGUCUGAUUAAACAUCCCAAGAUGUUUUCCAUGAGCUAGGGCCAUGAGUACCUUGUUUUUGACUGGAAGGAGCUGUGGGGUGGACCGUUUCCCUGAAAGCUAGAAGAAUGUUUGAAGCCUGUUCCCAAGGACCCUUGAACAUCUGUGAAGAAAUGACUAUUCUGCAUGGAGGCUUCUUGCUGGCCGAGCAGCUGUUCCACCCUAAGGCACUGGCAGAAUUAACAAAGUCUGACUGGGAACGUGUUGGACGGCCCAUCGUGGAGGCCUUAAGGGAGAUCUCCUCGGCUGCAGCACACUCCCAGCCCUUUGCCUGGAAGAAGAAAGCCCUGAUCAUCAUCUGGGCCAAGGUUCUGCAGCCGCACCCCGUGACCCCGUCCGACACAGAGACACGGUGGCAGGAAGACCUGUUCUUCUCGGUGGGCAACAUGAUCCCCACCAUCAACCACACCAUCCUCUUCGAGCUGCUCAAAUCCCUGGAAGCUUCUGGACUCUUUAUCCAGCUCCUGAUGGCCCUGCCCACCACCAUCUGCCAUGCAGAACUAGAGCGCUUUCUGGAACAUGUGACCGUUGACACUUCUGCCGAAGACGUGGCCUUCUUCCUGGACGUCUGGUGGGAGGUGAUGAAGCACAAGGGUCACCCGCAGGACCCCCUGCUCUCCCAGUUUAGUGCAAUGGCCCAUAAGUACCUGCCUGCCUUAGAUGAGUUCCCCCAUCCUCCAAAGAGGCUUAGGUCAGACCCAGACGCGUGCCCCACCAUGCCCCUGUUGGCCAUGCUGCUCCGCGGGCUGACACAGAUCCAGAGUCGGAUCCUGGGCCCGGGGAGGAAGUGCUGUGCGCUGGCCAACCUGGCUGACAUGCUGACUGUGUUUGCGCUGACAGAGGACGACCCCCAGGAGGUGUCUGCAACCGUGUAUCUGGACAAACUGGCCACGGUGAUCUCUGUGUGGAACUCGGACACCCAGAAUCCCUACCACCAGCAGGCGCUGGCAGAGAAGGUGAAGGAGGCAGAACGGGAUGUCAGCCUGACCUCGCUGGCCAAACUCCCCAGUGAGACCAUUUUCGUGGGCUGCGAGUUCCUGCACCACCUGCUGCGGGAGUGGGGGGAGGAGUUGCAGGCCGUGCUCCGCAGCAGCCAGGGGACAAGUUACGACAGCUACCGGCUGUGCGACAGUCUGACUUCCUUCAGCCAGAACGCGACGCUCUACCUGAACCGCACCAGCCUGUCCAAGGAGGACAGGCAGGUGGUCUCUGAGCUGGCGGAGUGUGUCAGGGACUUCCUGAGGAAAACGAGCACGGUGCUGAAGAACAGGGCCUUGGAGGAUAUCACAGCUUCCAUUGCCAUGGCCGUCAUCCAGCAGAAGAUGGACCGCCAUAUGGAAGUGUGCUACAUUUUUGCCUCUGAGAAGAAGUGGGCCUUCUCGGACGAGUGGGUAGCCUGCCUGGGGAGUAACAGGGCCCUCUUCCGACAGCCAGACUUGGUGUUGAGGCUGCUGGAAACAGUGAUAGACGUCAGCACAGCUGACAGAGCCAUCCCUGAGUCUCAGAUCCGGCAGGUGAUCCACCUGAUCCUGGAAUGUUACGCAGACCUCUCCCUGCCAGGUAAAAAUAAAGUCCUUGCAGGUAUCCUGCGUUCCUGGGGGCGAAAGGGCCUCUCUGAAAAGUUGCUGGCUUAUGUGGAGGGUUUUCAGGAAGACCUCAAUACAACUUUUAACCAGCUCACUCAGAGUGCCUCCGAACAGGGCUUGGCAAAAGCUGUGGCCUCCGUGGCCCGCCUGGUCAUAGUGCACCCGGAAGUCACGGUGAAGAAAAUGUGCAGCCUGGCUGUGGUCAAUCUCGGCACCCACAAGUUCCUGGCCCAGAUUCUCACUGCCUUCCCUGCCCUUAGGUUUGUGGAAGAGCAGGGUCCCAAUUCAUCUGCCACUUUCAUGGUGUCAUGCCUCAAAGAAACCGUCUGGAUGAAGUUCUCUACACCCAAGGAAGAAAAGCAAUUUUUAGAGCUCCUGAACUGCCUGAUGAGUCCCGUGAAACCCCAAGGGAUUCCAGUGGCUGCUCUUCUUGAGCCAGACGAGGUGCUGAAGGAAUUUGUCCUGCCUUUCUUGAGGUUAGAUGUUGAAGAGGUAGACCUCAGUCUGAGGAUCUUCAUCCAGACUCUAGAGGCAAACGCGUGCCGAGAGGAAUACUGGCUCCAGACCUGCUCCCCGUUUCCACUCCUCUUCAGCUUGUGCCAGCUCUUGGACCGCUUCAGCAAAUACUGGCAGCUUCCCAAGGAGAAGCGGUGCCUCUCUUUGGAUAGGAAGGAUCUAGCGAUCCAUAUCCUGGAGCUCCUGUGUGAGAUUGUAUCAGCCAAUGCUGAGACCUUCUCCCCGGAUGUCUGGAUCAAGUCCCUGUCCUGGCUCCACCGCAAGUUAGAACAGCUAGACUGGACUGUGGGCCUGAGGCUGAAGAGCUUCUUCGAGGGGCACUUCAAGUGUGAAGUGCCAGCCACACUUUUUGAGAUCUGUAAGCUUUCAGAAGACGAGUGGACCUCCCAGGCCCACCCAGGGUACGGGGCUGGCACGGGGCUCCUGGCCUGGAUGGAGUGCUGCUGCGUCUCCAGCGGCAUCUCGGAGAGGAUGCUGUCUCUCUUGGUGGUGGACGUGGGCAAUCCUGAGGAGGUCAGACUGUUCAGCAAAGGCUUUCUGGUGGCCCUGGUGCAAGUCAUGCCUUGGUGCAGCCCUCAGGAGUGGCAGCGCCUUCACCAGCUGACCAGGAGACUGCUGGAGAAGCAGCUCCUCCAUGUCCCUUAUAGCCUGGAAUAUAUUCAGUUUGUUCCCCUGCUCAACCUGAAGCCCUUUGCCCAGGAGUUGCAACUCUCCGUCCUCUUCCUGAGGACUUUCCAGUUUCUCUGCAGCCAUAGCUGUCGUGAUUGGCUUCCUCUGGAAGGCUGGAACCACGUGGUCAAACUCCUCUGUGGCAGUCUGACCCGCCUCCUGGACUCAGUCAGGGCGAUACAGGCAGCUGGCCCUUGGGUUCAAGGACCAGAGCAGGACCUGACCCAGGAAGCCCUGUUUGUUUACACCCAGGUGUUCUGCCAUGCUCUGCACAUCAUGGCCAUGCUCCACCCGGAGGUCUGUGAGCCACUCUACGUUUUAGCCUUGGAAACCCUCACCUGCUAUGAGACUUUGAGCAAGACCAACCCUUCUGUCAGCUCCUUGCUCCAGAGGGCACACGAGCAGCGCUUCUUAAAGUCCAUUGCUGAGGGCAUCGGCCCUGAAGAACGGCGCCAAACCCUGUUGCAGAAGAUGAGCAGCUUCUGACUUGGCGUGGGGAGCUGGGCCCCAACAUGGCGGGUCUGCAGAAGAUCAGCAGCUUCUUACCUGUGCGGGAGCGAAAAAGCUGGGCUUCAACAUGGCAGGUCUGUAGGGGUCAGACCCGAGCAGCCUGGACUUUACAGUUAUGUGAAACUGUCCACAAAAAGUCAUGGCAAUAAUGGUGUAAAGAAAAUAGUUUCUUGGGUAUUUGUAACGUACAAACUAUCAUAAAAAUUCUCCUCUUUCGCAUCUCACUUUGUCUCUUCUAAGUCGGCCUCAGCAAUAGCCCAGGAUUAAAUAUGCUCUGAAAUUGGGUUUAGUGUCUUCAAGAUCAAAUCCAGCCAGGAGGAACAUGUUCAUAACUGGACUUUUCCAUCCUAGAUUUUGGCAAAUAAGCCCAAAGUUGAAACCAUGUGAGUGGAAAAAGCAUUACAUGGUACGUAUAACCCCC